UUGAGAGAGAGAGAGAGAGAGAGCAAGGUGGAGAAGGAAGCAGAGAAAGGGAAAGGGUGAGGGAGCUACAGAGGGAGAGCAACAGAGCCUUGGAGAGGGAGGCUCUAUCUGGUAGACAGGGUCCCCUUUGCCAGGGUAGGGUGGAGGGUGACUGGGCCGGGCUGGAACAGGGGGGCAGGGCCGCCACUGCGGGAAAAUCAACGGAGCCCUGAGACGUGUUUUUACUUGGAUUGGUUGGUGGCCUUGGGGGUGCGUUUCGUAGCGUCAUUCUUUUUUUGGCUCCUCCCUGUCCUCUUGGUGCUGUGGGCCCUGAAAGUUGUAGAGUGCGCCCCUCACUGUGGCAGGAGCAGUGGCGCUGAGCGUGCCCACGGGCCGCGGCUUGGGUCUCUCGUUUUCCGGGUGGUAUGGCCUUAGACAAUGGCAGUGGCGCCUGGCUGGCCCAAGAGCCCGGUCCAGCUACGCCCGCCUGAUUCCAGGCGUCACCACCAACCCGGGGCCGCGAGGCUGGGAUCAGGCACCCCGGAGCCGCUUGCCCGUGGCCGGGCUGCUCUCCCCCUCUACGCCCAAGCACCACCAGUCGCCGCGCUGCGCUUUCUGCCGACCUCCCAGAGCGUCCAGCUGUCGCUGGCGGCCAGACCACGCGCGAGACCUACGCGGUGCCAGAGGCCUCCAUCCCCUGCCAGGGCUCUGGACUCUCCAUGCGACCACCCUCUCGCUGACACUCCAGGCCUUCCCCAGGCUCUGGAGCUCCAGAGCUUCCAACACCUGGGGCCCGCUCAGGACGGGGUGUGCUCCGAGGCGUCAGGGCCCAGGGCCCAGGGUCCUGGGGUACCCUCUGGUCCUCCGCCUUGCCGCGGAAAAAUUAUUUUGGAUUCCUCGCCGCCCCUCCUGCAAGGCCCCCUCUUGCCCCACACACCCAGAGCCGCCAGGGCUGCCCAGGGGCUAACAGCCGGCCCAGCCCCGCGGGCCCUUUUUCUCACAACGCCCACACCAUCGUCGCUUGUUCCGACGAGGACCCGCCGUGGCCAACGGGGCAGGAAGGCUCUGCUUUGCCCCGUGCUAGCACUAGAGCCCCGGCAGCCUCAUCCCGGGAAAGAGGGGCUGACGGACACCCAGACACACCCCACCACUACCACGAGCAAACCCCCCCUGACACACACACGGAUAGACACGGGUGCACGCGCGCGGACACACACACACCACACCCGUGCACACACACACGGACACACAAAGACACAGACACAGAGAGCUUGAAGGGAGACCACCCCUCAUAUUGUCUUAUGCCCAAUUUCUGCCUCCAAAGAAAGAAGUAAAAUCUAAAAGGCAGAAAUGAAAUCCACAGGCAGACAGCCCUGCGCCACACCCUGGGCCUGGUAGUUAAAGAUCGACCCCUGACCUACUCGAUUAUGUUAUCUAUAGAUUACAGACAUUAUAUAGAAAAGCACUGUGAAAAUCCCUGUCCUGUUUUGUUCUGAUCUAAUUACCGGUGCAUGCAGACCCCCGUCCCGUACCCUCUGCUUCCUCAAUCCAUCACGACCCCCUCACACGGACCCCCUUAGAGUUGUAAGCCCUUAAGAGGGACAGGAAUUGCUUACUCAGAGAGCUAGGUUUUUGGAGACGUGAGUCUGCCUAUGCUCCCAGCUGAAUAAAGCCCUCCCUUCUACAA